AGCAGCUUGCAAAUGGCGUCUCCCUCGCUGGAGCGGCCAGAAAAAGGCGCUGGAAAAAGUGAAUUUCGUAACCAGAAGCCGAAGCCGGAGAACCAAGGUGAUGUUAUGUGGGAACCGAAGCCUGGGGUUUGUAUGAAUCAGAACUCCUUACGGUUCCUGAUGGUUGGAAGGAACCAGCUUUUUCCAAAGAGGACAAUCCCAGAGGACUUUUGGAGGAGAGCAGUUUCGCAACUUUGUUCCCAAAAUACAGGGAAGCUUACUUGAAAGAGUGUUGGCCAUUGGUGCAGAAAGCCUUAAAUGAACAUCAUGUUAAUGCAACCCUGGACCUGAUCGAAGGCAGCAUGACUGUUUGUACUACAAAGAAGACUUUUGAUCCAUAUAUCAUCAUUAGGGCCAGAGAUCUGAUAAAACUGUUAGCAAGGAGUGUUUCAUUUGAACAGGCAGUACGAAUUCUUCAGGAUGAUGUUGCAUGUGACAUCAUUAAAAUAGGUUCUUUAGUAAGGAAUAAAGAGAGAUUUGUAAAACGAAGACAACGGCUUAUUGGUCCCAAAGGAUCUACAUUGAAGGCAUUGGAACUCUUAACUAAUUGUUACAUUAUGGUUCAGGGAAACACAGUUUCAGCCAUUGGACCUUUUAGUGGCUUAAAAGAGGUUAGAAAAGUAGUCCUUGAUACUAUGAAGAAUAUUCAUCCAAUUUAUAACAUUAAAAGCUUAAUGAUUAAGAGAGAGUUGGCAAAAGAUUCUGAAUUACGAUCACAAAGUUGGGAGAGAUUUUUGCCACAGUUCAAACACAAAAAUGUGAAUAAACGCAAGGAACCAAAGAAAAAAACUGUUAAGAAAGAAUAUACGCCAUUCCCACCACCACAACCAGAAAGUCAGAUCGAUAAAGAAUUGGCUAGUGGUGAAUACUUUUUGAAGGCAAAUCAGAAGAAGCGGCAGAAAAUGGAAGCAAUAAAGGCUAAACAAGCAGAAGCCAUCAGUAAGAGACAAGAGGAAAGAAACAAAGCAUUUAUUCCACCUAAGGAAAAACCAAUUGUGAAACCUAAGGAAGCUUCUACUGAAACUAAAAUUGAUGUGGCCAGCAUCAAGGAAAAGGUUAAGAAAGCAAAGAAUAAGAAACUGGGAGCUCUUACAGCUGAAGAAAUUGCACUUAAGAUGGAGGCAGAUGAAAAGAAAAAGAAGAAAAAAAAGUAACAUACCCAAAACUCCUUGACUAGAACUAUCUCCUUUUGUAAAGGAUUUUGAGAUAUCAGGCAUUAGUUGCCUUAUUUGUGAGAAAUUUUCUGAGGGCUUUUUUUUUUUUUGGUGGUGGUGGUUGUUCAUAGAAGAGUGUUCUUUAUAAAUUAUAUUAUUAUUGUAUUUUUUGAAAAAUUUAUACGAGAAAGUGGUAUAUAAGUCUUUGUAUACAUUACGACCAUUGUGAUUAUCCAUUAAAUCCAGUGUCUGAUGCUAUUGGUUAGUAAUGAUGUCCCAGCAUUUGAUGUUCCCUCUCUAAUGAUAACAAGUAAAUAUUUAGGUUUAUCCCUUUUGAAAGUUUGGUUUUACUUUUAACAGUCCAUGAACAGAAAAUUAAGGCCUCUAAAAUCAGAUCCCCUAGUUACUCCUCUGUUCUGAAUCUGGGGAAGUAGUAAACCAAAAAGACAGGGAAAACCAGAUAUUUAGAGUCGAAGCAGCAUGCAAAAAAUAAUAAUGUUUUUAACUAAUGAAGGCUACUGGAGUUACUAAGAAUCACCUAAAAAUGUGCUACUGUACCUUGCUCAUUUUGCAGAUUUAGAAGCUGAAACAUGGGUUAGGUUACUUACUAAAAGUCCACCUGUGGCAACCUGCAAAUAAUGCUUAUUUAUACUAAAGAUGAGUUUAUCUGAUAGAGUUAGGAAAUUUCUUCUUUUGAGUAAGAGUAUUGCUAUAACAUAUAUUUUUUUCUGAAAUGUUUUAAAAUAGAAGUACACCUAAUUGUUAUUGGUUAAAAAAAAAGCCAUAUGUGAAUGAGGUUGGUUUUUGGGUUUUUUCUUUCCUGAAUUGUAUUAGUCCAAAAGAACUAAAUUAGGGUACUUGUGCUGUACCAAAAUGGUAAUUAUAACAGACAGUAUUAGAAUUACUGAAUUAACAAUGAGAAAGAGAGAAGUGUAUCUGUUACGUGGAUAUAUGGGCCAGCCUGGAUAUACAACAGAGUAGUAACCUGUGAAACAAACAUAGAAUAUCCUCUUAGACAUUGUUCCUCAUAAUGCACUGACAGAAUUCACAUAGCUCUUAAUGAAACAAUUUAAGAUUGAUGUACGUACGUUUGACUUGGUCUCGCUGUCGGUUAACUGUAAAGUUAGGGGGAAGAAAGAAAAAAAAUUAAAAGGGUAGACACAGUUGAGAGUUUUAUUUUAAAAAGCUAAGUCUUAUAAUUAUGACCAUUAACUUGCUUUGGCUUUAUUGCAGUGACUUUCCAAGUUUAAUUAUUCAAAACUUUUUGAACUGACUGAAUUAACUUGGUAUUUUUAAGUUGACUUUUUACAUAAACUUUAUAAACCUUUUAUAAAAAGGAAACUAUACCAUUACUAUAAAUGGAAAAUCAUUUUACACAUCAUACCUAGCAGGUAAUAAAAUUUAAAAAAUAAAAAUUAAAUAUUAGAAUGUGAGAAAUUUAUUAAAAUAUAGUUCUAAAAAUAAGUUUCUUCCUGAGAAGAAUGAUACUGUUUAUGAUGAAUCCAUAGUGAAAAGACAGUGACCUCUCUUUCAUCCAGUCUAGUAUAUCACUAAAUCAUCAUUACGAUGUUUGGCUAUCAAGUCAUUAAUUACUGUCCUCCUUUCACUGAGCUUUAUUCAAAUUUUGACAAUCAGAGCACUGGGAAGAAAUAAAUUCCACAACUGCCUUUAGCCUUCUGGAUACUUUCUUUUAUAAAAUAGAAACCUUUUCCACACCAGUUCUGCAGCAGUCGCUAUUAGAUGCUCGUGGUAGAACCCAUCAAUCAUCUGGUCCUCUGGGUACUGGUGAGCAUCCCUGGUCUUCAUACCUGUGAGUGGGCUUUGUGGUGAAUUACUGUAAAUAUGCUACCCUCACUUUUCUUGGCAGUUAUGUCGAUGAAAUCAAGAGUGUGAUGUUCUAGUUAUUUUUUUUUAUAUAUAUUUUUAAAUGUUCAAUAUUCAACUAUUGAAACAAAUGUACAUCUGUGAACUAGCUAAAAUCAUCUUAUGUACCACUAAUAUGCCCAGCACAUUUUGUAAAACAGUCCUGAUUUGGCCUCCAAGGGUAUUUAUUGAACUACCAGCAGUAUCUAGGAGACCACGAAGGAAUACCACGAAGGAAUUUAUGCUCCAGUGCUUGCCAUAAUUUGUCUGAGAAGGAAUCUGUUAAAUAAAAGCUUUUAUCCUCUAACCUUUACCUUCAUCAGACCUUAUAAAAGGUCAAAUGGUGAUUCUUAAGUUUUUUAGUCACAAAUCUUACUUAUUCAGUAUUAGUGCGAAGAGUAGAAUACUUUCAAGUAAGCCUAAACUUACAUGAAAACAAAUUACAUAAAUCUAGCUCUGAGAAUAGGAAAUUAGUGACAAGAUCAAUCUGUAAGAUGUUGAGCACUUAUCUGAAGUAAAUGGGUAAUGAGUUUCACAUCUUAUAAAUACAAGUUAGCAUGUGUUUUCUCAAGAGUCCAAGGGUUUUCAUUAUUGGACUACAGCUUUAAUCUUCUAAAUGUUAUUCCCCAAGAUUAAAGAGCAUCUCAAGUUAGAUCACCAAAGAUCAAAAGCUAAAACCAGAAGUAUUUUUGUCAUUGUGGUGGUGGUAGUGUUACUAAUUGCCUAGAUUUUUAAAGGGAAACAUUUUUUUCACUGGGUUGUUUCGUUGAAAAAAAUAGAAGCAGAAACUUGCCCAAAGUCACAGUGGUCAAACUGGAAAUUGCACCAAAACUUGGCAUACUGGUUCUGAAAUCCAUAGUUUUAGCCCUUAUGUAUACUGGUUAAUUUGGAAGGAAGAAAUAUAUACGUUCUGAAGUGAAGAGUGAGUGAAAGGAAGAAUUCAGUGAAUACAUUGAUACCUUGAUAUUAUCUGCAUUGUGGCUACAUGUUACUUUUCUUCACAAGAGUGAUAUAAGUGAAAUAAAGAAUGAUUGGACUGGGAGAAAAAUGGCUCAGAAAACUUUGCAAAAGUACGACUGUAUGUAAAGAUAAGUAUUCAACAUUAAAUGGGAAGGAGGAGAGCAAGCAGUUUAAUAUAUAGAAUUUUAUAAUUUUAGGCCUGCAAGGGACCUUAUAAAACAUGAGCAAUGGAACACUUUUUUCCAAACUAAAUUUCGUGCAGUGGAACUUGGCCGACUCUGUCCUUCCUCUAUUCUAAGCACCCUACUCUAGCCCGGCUGCUCUGAGUUCAGUUUGUUACAAAUAUGGACACGAAAGUACCACAGGCUUUGCACAGCUUAAUUGAAGUUUCCCCUUCACACCAUGGUAAAAAAACAUACUGGGAUGGAAGGGUUUGUGUCUAGAACAAGAACAAGAAAUAAACUCUUGGUCACUUACUAAUAUUUCAAAAUCACAAAGCAGAAUUUUGCUUGGAUGUUUAGUAAAACAUCCUUGGAAAUUUAACUGCUUGCAGCUUCUACACUUCUUCAUUAAAUGCUGUCUGGCUAAUAAAAAGUGCCAUGUUGCAGCUUUAUUUUAUUUUCAUUUUUUGGAGAUAGACCCUCACUGUGUCACCCAGGCUGGAGUGCAGUGGUACAAUCUCUGCUCACUGCAACCUCCACCUCCUGGGCUCAAGUGAUUGUCCUGCCUCAGCCUCCUGAGUAGCUGGGGUUACGGGCGUCCACCACCACACCCAGCUAGUUUUUGUAUUUUUAGUAGAGGGGGUUUUUGCCAUGUUGGCCAGGCUGGGCAUGGUGGCAUGGUAAUCUCAGCUACUUGGGAGGCUGAGGCAGGAGGAUCGCCUGAACCCGUGAGAUGGAGGUUGCAGUGAGCUGAGAUCACACCACUGCACUCUAGCAUGGGUGACAGAGCAAGACUCUGUCUCAAAAAAAAAAAACAAAAAAAAAAACGAAAACAGAAUUCUGUUUGUUUGGAUGACCUGUUAUACUUAUUUUUGAUCUUGCUGAAAUAAGCAAAUCUUAGGAAUCUUAGUCUACAGUUUCUGACAGUUUUUUUUGUUGUUGUUGUUUGACCAAUUAGAACUAAAUAAAAAGAACGUGAUUUUCACAUUUAAAUUUCUCUUAAAUGUAUUCCUAGAACAGUAAGCCAUUGGUUUAAUUGCUACUUGAUGCCAGUUUCCUUGAAGAUAGCCGUUAAGAUAAAACAUGGUUUCAUUGUUAAUUCUGUAGAAAGUUACAUGUUACUAUUAUGUUAUUCUAUUGGUGUAUUGUUCCUUUUACUCACCACAGAGAUUGUCCAAACACUUGUCAUUAUUGGGGCAGGCACUGCAGGUGGCUCCUCUCUUAUAUGGCCAAGUUGGGUAAUUCCCUCUGUAAAGCAGAAGAAGGAUGUCCAUUAGAAGUUUUUCGGUUUUUUAAAAUUGCAAUUUACUAUGAAUCCUUAACUAAAUCCAGAAGAAUAGUGGAGUGAAGUACAAAGGUCCAGAGAGUUGGUAAUAGAAGUGAAGACAGGAAGGCAGAAAUGGAAGGCUGCUAAUAUUUGCAUAGUUCAUUCUAUGUACCUGUGUCUAUGCACCUGUUUUAAUCUGCAUCCCAUUUAAUUGUGACAGCUCUGAGAGGAAGUUAUUCUUGUUUUACAGAUGAGACAAAAGAUGUAAGAGAUACCUUUAAUCACAAUUUAUACACUUCAGAGUCAGAGGAAACCUGGAUUUAACUCCAGGGCUGUGCUCCCUCUCUUUACCUACCCUCUGGCCUAUAUGAUUACUGCCAUUUAAAAAACUGUCCAUCUUAGAAAAGCUAUGGUGACCCACAUUCAAUAUUCUCAGUUGGUCAGCCCUCCAUAAUUUUCACUGGAUAGGAGCCAUUUGGCUGGUGCCUUCCAAAAAAAUAAUAAAUAAUGGUAUGGGGGAAUUUCUAAAGUACAAAUUGUUUUCACAUACAAGAUGUGAUAUGAAUAAUAGCUGCUAAUUAGUGAGCACUACCAUGUGCUUGUCUUUGUUCUAAACAACCUUGAAUGAAAUAAUCUUCACAAAAACCCUAUGAGGAAGUUACUGUUGUCUAUUUAUACCCAUUAUAUAGCUAGAGGCUGAGUCACAGAGUAUAAGUAAUUGACCAAGGUCACAGACUAGAAAGUGAAAUAAUAUCCAAGCAUUUUAUAUCCCCAUAAAUAUCCUCAUAGUAGUAAUGGGGAGAGGGGGCACAUUUAUCUCAAUGAACCUGCCAUUGCACUAAUUUUUUUUGGAACUCUGCUUUUGGAAAAAGUUCUAAACUUUUUUGUGUAAUCGUACCCUUUGGCAGUCUGGUGAGGCCUAUGGGCUCUUUCUCAACAUAGUUUGUUGUUAAAUGCAUAAAAUACAUAGGAUUAUAAAGGAAACCAAUUAAAUUGAAAUAGUUAUCAAAAUGUUUAAAACAAGAUUUGUGAUAAAGUAAUAUGUGCUUCUCUAUUAAGAUCUACCGGGGGCUAUUAGUUUCAAUGCAGUGAUGAACACAAACUAUAUUUUGAGUUCUCUGCAGCAAGUGGAAUGUGGUAUGAAAAUAUCUGAUAUUUACAAAGAUGAUACUGCUAAGUCAGAGUCACGUUUAUUGCUAAUAUGAUGGUGGAGUGUUGUCUUCAUUCAUAAUGAAAGGAAAUGUUAUUUUUAAUAGAGGUUAGUGAAAAUAAAAAUAAAACUAUUUUCUAAUCAAAGUUUAUGGUCCUCCUCUCCCCAGCACUCUACAAUUACCUCCAAAGUUGAGAACUCUCACCUUAGACACACAACUUUAUAACGAUACCUUAUUUCCAACCCCAAAUCUAUGUUCUUAUCUCAUUUUGCUCCAAAUUUUAAGUUGCUUCAGAAAUUUAAUUAGCCCUCUGCUUACUCUACACCAUGGAAAAAAGGUAAUAUAGUAGAAAUUCUGAUAGCAAUUUCAAAAGAUGUCCAAAAUAGACAUUAAUCAUUGGAAUGUCUUUCAUUGUUAAUAAGCACAGUAUUAAGUGGUUUAAGUUCUAGAAUGAUUUUAAUAAAGUCAUUUAUGAUACUUAGUUGUGCAUUCCAAACUGUAAAGGAAAAGGUAAAAAAUGCUACUUAAAAAUAAGCUAAAAACCAAGACAGUCGGUGAGGUCUGUGGAAAUGGUAGUAUUCAUCUUGGGAGAAACAUGCUACUGGAAAGGCCUGGAUUUGUCUAGAUGGGAGUCAUUAAGACUGUGGGACCUAAAGUAUUCAGCACAAUAAAGCAACAGGACAUUUCAAUGUUUUCCCUGGUAGCCUGAGAGAGAAGAGGGUUGGGGUUAUGGGACCCAGGGGAAGACCGAAGACAAAUCUUUAAAGAAAAAGAUAAAUAUGGGUAAGGGUCCCUAAGGCAGUGACGGCCUAAGCACACUGGUACUAUCUUGACUAUCUUGUGGUCAAAGUUAUUUCCUCUUCUGUGCUAUAAUCCUCUCCUCCACUAAUCCACUCUGAGUAAAGAUCUGUUACACACCAUACCCUUGUUCAUGGUGCCCAGGGGAAAUGAAGAGGAGAGUAUUACAGGCAACUGGAAGAUUAAGCAUCCCAGACCCCAUUCUGAGGUAUCAGAAAUAUUGAGGAGGAUACUGGACUUCCUAAGAUUAUGUGGAAUGGGGGCCUACAACUUUUUGUGUAUAGGAAAAUAAUACCUCAGAGGGCAGAGGGCAAAGGGAAAUGAGGACAUUCCUAACUGGUCUCUCUGUUUUACCUUUUAUGCUCCUCUAAUCCAUUUUCCAUCCAGACUGAUGUCCAAAUUUAAAGGUCUCAUCGCUCCCCUGCUUAAUAUACUUGAAUGACUUCUUAUGUAAACUUUGUCAUGAUCUAAAAGUUCCCGCUAGAUCUGCAACUGCCUUCCUCCCCCCGUUUCAUCUGUUUAGCAGACCGAGGGCACCAGUCUCUGUGGUUUAAACUUGCCAAACUUUUCUUCACGGAAGUUUUGCUGUUCUUUUCUCCACUAGACAGCUGUUCCAGAAGUUCUUAUGUCUGAUUCCUUCUCAUUCUUCAUGCCUAAGCUUAAAUAUAACACAAGAAGCCCUUCCCUGAUUAUUCUAAACAGGGGCCUUGCCUAUUGAUAGUUUCUAUUACAGUAUUAUUUAUAGUUCCUUAAUUGCCCCAUAAUGAUGCAGUUAUUUUACUUGUAUUUUUAUUAUCUGUUUGCCCCAUAAAUAUUACUCUCAUAAAGACAGAGACUGCCCUGUUCUCCUUUGGAGCUCAGUAAAACAAAUAUUUGUUGAAUAAAUGAAUAUUUGAAGUUAGUCUUUAUGGAAGCAUUAUAACUUUGGUUGUAAGUUUUAUAAUUUAAUAUUGUUUAUAACUCUGAAGAUAAGUGAGUCUAAACCAGGAAAAUUUACAUUUAUACUUUAAUGAAUAAAAAUCAUGAAUACUUACAAAACAUUCACUAUUGCCAAGCAUUAUAUAUACCUAGUAUUUUACAAAGCCUUCUCUUGUCACUUUCAUAGCUACUCUAAGUGAUGGGUCCUGUAACCCUGAUCUAUUGGAGGUUAAACUGAGAUUCAGAGUUAACUUGUCCAGGGUCACACAGUAAAUUAAUUGUAUCUUAACCAUUAAAAAUGUCAUAUGAGGCCGGGUGUAGUGGCUCAUGCCUAUAAUCCCAGCACUCUGGGAGGCUGAGGCAGGUGGAUCACUUUAGCCCAGGAGUUGGAGAUGAGCCUGGGCAAUAUGGCAAAACUCUGUCUCUACAAAAAAAUUAACUGGGCAUGGUGGCAUGUGCCUGUAGUCUCAGGUACUAGGAAGGCUGAGUUGGGAGGAUUGCUUGAGCCUGGGAGGUUAAGCCUGCAGUGAACCGUAAGCGAGCCACUGUACUCCAGCCUGGGUGACAGAGUGAGAGACCCUGUCUCAAAAAAAAAAAAAAAAGUCAUGAAAAGUUACCACUAACUGAAUUAUGGCUUUGUCUAGUUUUUUCUGGGUUUUCUUUAUUUUCCAACUCUUAAGAUAUUAAGUCAAAGCUGUCAUCUUCAGAAUGACGCUUUGUCUCCUCCUUCACACCUACAGCACUCAGUCAGAGUAUCGAGCAUGUCUUCUGCACAUUACACCAGGGAAAUGGCUUUCUUUCAGCCAAUCUCCAGGAAUCCAAAAAUUCAAAGGCAACAAAUUAAAGAUCAUUAUAUAUAUUGCAAAUGGUUAAAAACCUUUAAAAUAUAAAAACUUUUAUAAAUAAGAAAAUCUAGUAGAAAAAUGGUCAGCCCACAUGAUUCACAGAAAAAGGAAUAUAAAUAGACAAUUAUGUGAAGAAAUUUAUAAUUACUAGUAAUCACAGAGAUGCAAAAGAAAGCAAAUGAAAUGCCAUUUCCAUCAAAUUAGAAAAUACUAAGAAAUUAUAAUACCUAGUACUGAUGGUGAAAUACAAAUUGAUAUAAUGGUGGAAUGUAAUUUGGCAAUAUGUACUUAAAACAAAAAUGGUCACAGUCUUUACGUGCUAGUAUCUCAAGGAAUUAUAGGGAAAUAGAAGUGACUGAAGAUACAUAUAUGAGGUUGUUCAUCAUAUAUUAAAUGAAAAUAUAGUGAACAAUCUAAAUUCUUCAACAGGAUGGUGGUACCAUCAAGAGCAUGGACUCUGGAGCUAGACAGCCAGAUCAAAGUCCAUCAGUGAUAGUCACUAACUGUAGAACUUUGGGCAGGUUGCUGACCCGUGUGUGCCUUGCUGUUCUCAUUUGCCAAACAGGGGUAGUAAUAGGAGCCAUCUCAUAAACUUCUGGUGAAGAUUAAGUUAAUAUAUGUGAAGCACUUUAACAGUGCUGAGAGCAUUGUAAGCAUUAUAUAAACAAUCUAUCAUUUUUAUGAUUAAAAUCACUUAAAAUUUUGAAAAGGAAAAUUUUUCACAGCAUAAUUUUAAGUGAAAAAUAGAAAAUGUAUAUUUUCAGUAUGAUCAGAUUUCUAAAUAUGUGUAUGACACAAGCACACAUAUGUAAGUUUAAAGAAAGUAGGAGGAAGGUGUUUGCCCUGUUUCCCAAAGUGGGAACUAUAUCUGUUUUAAAAACAACUGUCAAAAGUAAAUGAAAUAGGUUAUAUAAGUUGAGGAAUCUGUUUUGCUUUGAAAAUUGUGUAAAAUUGCCAAGUUUCUAAUAAACCAAUAAAUAUAA